AGAAAGAAGAAAACCAGCUCCCACACAGAGCCUCCCGGCUGCGCAGACCUUUCCCAGCACAGCGGAUUGCCAGCUCCGAGACCCGGGACUCCUCCUGUCCUGGGCCGAAUGCUCUUUUAGCGCGGUAGAGUGCACUUUCUCCAACUGGAAAAGCGGGGACCCAGCGAGAACCCGAGCGAACGAUGGGAGGGAGCUGCGCGCAGAGGCGCCGGGCCGGCCCGCGGCAGGUGCUAUUUCCUUUGCUGCUGCCUUUGUUCUACCCCACCCUGAGUGAGCCGAUCCGCUACUCGAUUCCGGAGGAGCUGGCCAAGGGCUCGGUGGUGGGGAACCUCGCUAAGGAUCUAGGGCUCAGUGUCCUGGAUGUGUCGGCUCGCAAGCUGCGAGUGAGCGCGGAGAAGCUGCACUUCAGCGUAGACGCGGAGAGCGGGGACUUACUUGUGAAGAACCGAAUAGACCGUGAGCAAAUAUGCAAAGAGAGAAGAAGAUGUGAGUUGCAAUUGGAAGCUGUGGUGGAAAAUCCUUUAAAUAUUUUUCAUGUCAUUGUGGUGAUUGAGGAUGUUAAUGACCACGCCCCUCAAUUUGAUAAAAAGGAAAUACAUUUAGAAAUUUUCGAAUCUGCAUCCGCUGGUACACGACUAUCGCUUGACCCUGCCACGGAUCCUGAUAUAAACAUAAACUCAAUUAAAGAUUAUAAGAUAAACUCUAAUCCUUAUUUUUCAUUAAUGGUUAGAGUUAAUUCCGAUGGUGGCAAAUACCCAGAGUUAUCUCUGGAGAAACUCCUAGACCGGGAAGAACAGAGAUCUCAUAGCUUGAUAUUGACUGCCUUGGACGGAGGGGACCCACCAAGAAGUGCCACCGCUCACAUAGAAAUUUCUGUCAAGGAUACCAAUGAUAACCCCCCGGUUUUCAGCAGAGACGAAUAUAGAAUUAGUCUUAGUGAAAAUCUGCCCCCUGGGUCCCCUGUGUUGCAAGUGACAGCCACUGACCAGGAUGAGGGGGUCAAUGCUGAGAUAAACUACUACUUCCGAAGCACUGCCCAGAGCACAAAACAUAUGUUCUCAUUGGAUGAGAAAACAGGUAUGAUUAAGAAUAACCAGUCAUUUGAUUUUGAAGAUGUAGAAAGGUACACCAUGGAAGUGGAAGCGAAGGACGGAGGUGGUCUCUCUACCCAGUGUAAAGUAAUCAUAGAAAUCCUUGAUGAAAACGACAACAGCCCAGAAAUAAUCAUCACUUCUCUCUCUGAUCAGAUUUUGGAGAAUUCACCUCCAGGAAUGGUUGUUGCCCUCUUCAAAACACGGGAUCUGGAUUUCGGAGGAAAUGGAGAAGUCAGGUGUAAUAUAGAAACAGACAUUCCAUUCAAGAUUUAUUCUUCUUCCAAUAACUACUACAAACUGGUGACAGAUGGAGCCCUGGACCGAGAGCAGACACCAGAAUACAAUGUCACCAUCGUAGCCACUGACAGGGGCAAGCCGCCUCUUUCUUCCAGUAGAAGCAUCACCUUGUAUGUCGCUGACAUCAACGACAACGCCCCAGUUUUCGACCAGACGUCCUACGUGGUCCACGUGGCCGAGAACAACCCGCCAGGAGCCUCCAUUGCGCAAGUGAGCGCCUCUGACCCGGAUUUGGGGCUCAAUGGCCACAUCUCCUACUCUAUAGUGGCGAGUGACCUAGAGCCCCUGGCGGUGUCGUCAUACGUGUCAGUGAGCGCGCAGAGCGGGGUGGUGUUCGCGCAGCGCGCCUUUGAUCACGAGCAGCUGCGCGCCUUCGCGCUCACGCUGCAGGCCCGCGACCACGGCUCGCCCACGCUCAGCGCCAACGUGAGCCUGCGCGUGUUGGUGGGAGACCGCAAUGACAACGCACCGCGGGUGCUGUACCCAGCUCUGGGUCCUGACGGCUCCGCGUUCUUCGAUAUGGUACCUCGCUCUGCAGAGCCCGGCUACCUAGUGACUAAGGUGGUAGCGGUGGACGCCGACUCGGGACACAACGCCUGGCUGUCCUACCACGUGCUGCAGGCCAGUGAGCCCGGACUCUUCAGCCUGGGGCUGCGCACUGGGGAGGUGCGCACGGCUCGAGCCUUAGGCGACAGGGACGCAGCCCGCCAGCGCCUGCUGGUCGCUGUGCGUGACGGUGGACAGCCGCCACUCUCUGCCACCGCCACGCUUCAUCUGGUCUUCGCAGACAACUUGCAAGAGAUACUGCCAGACCUCAGCGACCGCCCUGUACUCUCUGACCCCCAGGCUGAACUGCAGUUUUACCUGGUGGUGGCCUUGGCCUUAAUCUCAGUGCUCUUCCUCCUCGCCGUGAUUCUGGCCAUUGCCUUGCGCCUGCGACGCUCUCUCAGCCCUGCUACUUGGGACUGCUUCCAUCCUGGUCUCUGUGUCAAGUCUGGACCUGUAGUUCCCCCCAACUACAGUGAGGGGACUUUGCCUUAUUCUUAUAAUCUGUGCAUUGCACAUACGGGUACAAAAGAGUUUAAUUUCCUAAAAUGCAGUGUGCCCCUACAUUCCAAUGAAGACAUGGUUUGCAGUGUUUCUCCUGGAGCCUUAAUUCCACCUCAUGGUGGGGAGGAUUUGACUUCACAUCCUGAGACUCUGACUUCGCAAGCCCCGCCCAACACGGACUGGCGUUUCUCUCAGGCCCAGAGACCCGGCACCAGCGGCUCCCAAAAUGGCGAUGACACCGGCACCUGGCCCAACAACCAGUUUGACACAGAGAUGCUGCAAGCCAUGAUCUUGGCGUCCGCCAGUGAAGCUGCUGAUGGGAGCUCCACCCUGGGAGGGGGUGCCGGCACCAUGGGAUUGAGCGCCCGCUACGGACCCCAGUUCACCCUGCAGCACGUGCCCGACUACCGCCAGAAUGUCUACAUCCCAGGCAGCAAUGCCACACUGACCAACGCAGCUGGCAAGCGGGAUGGCAAGGCCCCAGCAGGUGGCAAUGGCAACAAGAAGAAGUCGGGCAAGAAGGAGAAGAAGUAACAUGGAGGCCAGGCCAAGAGCCACAGGGCGGCCUCUCCCCAACCAGCCCAGCUUCUCCUUACCUGCACCCAGGCCUCAGAGUUUCAGGGCUAACCCCCAGAAUACUGGUAGGGGCCAAGGCCAUGCUCCCCUUGGGAAACAGAAACAAGUGCCCAGUCAGCACCUACCCCUUCCCCCCCAGGGGGUUGAAUAUGCAAAAGCAGUUCCGCUGGGAACCCCCAUCCAAUCAACUGCUGUACCCAUGGGGGUAGUGGGGUUACUGUAGACACCAAGAACCAUUUGCCACACCCCGUUUAGUUACAGCUGAACUCCUCCAUCUUCCAAAUCAAUCAGGCCCAUCCAUCCCAUGCCUCCCUCCUCCCCACCCCACUCCAACAGUUCCUCUUUCCCGAGUAAGGUGGUUGGGGUGUUGAAGUACCAAGUAACCUACAAGCCUCCUAGUUCUGAAAAGUUGGAAGGGCAUCAUGACCUCUUGGCCUCUCCUUUGAUUCUCAAUCUUCCCCCAAAGCAUGGUUUGGUGCCAGCCCCUUCACCUCCUUCCAGAGCCCAAGAUCAAUGCUCAAGUUUUGGAGGACAUGAUCACCAUCCCCAUGGUACUGAUGCUUGCUGGAUUUAGGGAGGGCAUUUUGCUACCAAGCCUCUUCCCAACGCCCUGGGGACCAGUCUUCUGUUUUGUUUUUCAUUGUUUGACGUUUCCACUGCAUGCCUUGACUUCCCCCACCUCCUCCUCAAACAAGAGACUCCACUGCAUGUUCCAAGACAGUAUGGGGUGGUAAGAUAAGGAAGGGAAGUGUGUGGAUGUGGAUGGUGGGGGCAUGGACAAAGCUUGACACAUCAAGUUAUCAAGGCCUUGGAGGAGGCUCUGUAUGUCCUCAGGGGACUGACAACAUCCUCCAGAUUCCAGCCAUAAACCAAUAACUAGGCUGGACCCUUCCCACUACAUAAUAGGGCUCAGCCCAGGCAGCCAGCUUUGGGCUGAGCUAACAGGACCAAUGGAUUAAACUGGCAUUUCAGUCCAAGGAAGCUCGAAGCAGGUUUAGGACCAGGUCCCCUUGAGAGGUCAGAGGGGCCUCUGUGGGUGCUGGGUACUCCAGAGGUGCCACUGGUGGAAGGGUCAGCGGAGCCCCAGCAGGAAGGGUGGGCCAGCCAGGCCAUUCUUAGUCCCUGGGUUGGGGAGGCAGGGAGCUAGGGCAGGGACCAAAUGAACAGAAAGUCUCAGCCCAGGAUGGGGCUUCUUCAACAGGGCCCCUGCCCUCCUGAAGCCUCAGUCCUUCACCUUGCCAGGUGCCGUUUCUCUUCCGUGAAGGCCACUGCCCAGGUCCCCAGUGCGCCCCCUAGUGGCCAUAGCCUGGUUAAAGUUCCCCAGUGCCUCCUUGUGCAUAGACCUUCUUCUCCCACCCCCUUCUGCCCCUGGGUCCCCGGCCAUCCAGCGGGGCUGCCAGAGAACCCCAGACCUGCCCUUACAGUAGUGUAGCGCCCCCUCCCUCUUUCGGCUGGUGUAGAAUAGCCAGUAGUGUAGUGCGGUGUGCUUUUACGUGAUGGCGGGUGGGCAGCGGGCGGCGGGCUCCGCGCAGCCGUCUGUCCUUGAUCUGCCCGCGGCGGCCCGUGUUGUGUUUUGUGCUGUGUCCACGCGCUAAGGCGACCCCCUCCCCCGUACUGACUUCUCCUAUAAGCGCUUCUCUUCGCAUAGUCACGUAGCUCCCACCCCACCCUCUUCCUGUGUCUCACGCAAGUUUUAUACUCUAAUAUUUAUAUGGCUUUUUUUCUUCGACAAAAAAAUAAUAAAACGUUUCUUCUGAAAA